CACUUGGGACGGGUCCCUGAGUAGGUGAGGAGGUGGGUAGGAGCUUGCUUAUAGAAAAGUGGAAUCGAGUAGUCCUUGCUGGUGGAGCCGCUGCCGCCAGGGAACUCAGGGCCGGCUCCUGUUCCUUCAAGAGUGCUGGAGGCCAAACUUGAAAUACAAGUUUAAUGUUCCUCGUCGGGCAAAAGAUAAGGAUCCGAUCUCCCCCGGCCCGGUGUGCAGCAGGAGCGACCAACCCCGACCCGGGUUAAAACUCCCAGGGACUCUUCGCUGCUGCCACCUCUUGUUCUCUCCCCCGUUCCCACUCGGGGUCUCCCUCAGGGCCGGGAGGCACAGCGGUCCCUGCUUGCUGAAGGGCUGGAUGUACGCAUCCGCAGGUUCCCGCGGACUUGGGGGCGCCCGCUGAGCCCCGGCGCCCGCAGAAGACUUGUGUUUGCCUCCUGCAGCCUCAACCCGGAGGGCAGCGAGGGCCUACCACCAUGAUCACUGGUGUGUUCAGCAUGCGCUUGUGGACCCCAGUGGGCGUCCUGACCUCGCUGGCGUACUGCCUGCACCAGCGGCGGGUGGCCCUGGCCGAGCUGCAGGAGGCCGAUGGCCAGUGUCCGGUCGACCGCAGCCUGCUGAAGUUGAAAAUGGUGCAGGUCGUGUUUCGACACGGGGCUCGGAGUCCUCUCAAGCCGCUCCCGCUGGAGGAGCAGGUAGAGUGGAACCCCCAGCUAUUAGAGGUCCCACCCCAAACUCAGUUUGAUUACACAGUCACCAAUCUAGCUGGUGGUCCGAAACCAUAUUCUCCUUACGACUCUCAAUACCAUGAGACCACCCUGAAGGGGGGCAUGUUUGCUGGGCAGCUGACCAAGGUGGGCAUGCAGCAAAUGUUUGCCUUGGGAGAGAGACUGAGGAAGAACUAUGUGGAAGACAUUCCCUUUCUUUCACCAACCUUCAACCCACAGGAGGUCUUUAUUCGUUCCACUAACAUUUUUCGGAAUCUGGAGUCCACCCGUUGUUUGCUGGCUGGGCUUUUCCAGUGUCAGAAAGAAGGACCCAUCAUCAUCCACACUGAUGAAGCAGAUUCAGAAGUCUUGUAUCCCAACUACCAAAGCUGCUGGAGCCUGAGGCAGAGAACCAGAGGCCGGAGGCAGACUGCCUCUUUACAGCCAGGAAUCUCAGAGGAUUUGAAAAAGGUGAAGGACAGGAUGGGCAUUGACAGUAGUGAUAAAGUGGACUUCUUCAUCCUCCUGGACAACGUGGCUGCCGAGCAGGCACACAACCUCCCAAGCUGCCCCAUGCUGAAGAGAUUUGCAAGGAUGAUCGAACAGAGAGCUGUGGACACAUCCUUGUACAUACUGCCCAAGGAAGACAGGGAAAGUCUUCAGAUGGCAGUAGGCCCAUUCCUCCACAUCCUAGAGAGCAACCUGCUGAAAGCCAUGGACUCUGCCACUGCCCCCGACAAGAUCAGAAAGCUGUAUCUCUAUGCGGCUCAUGAUGUGACCUUCAUACCGCUCUUAAUGACCCUGGGGAUUUUUGACCACAAAUGGCCACCGUUUGCUGUUGACCUGACCAUGGAACUUUACCAGCACCUGGAAUCUAAGGAGUGGUUUGUGCAGCUCUAUUACCACGGGAAGGAGCAGGUGCCGAGAGGUUGCCCUGAUGGGCUCUGCCCGCUGGACAUGUUCUUGAAUGCCAUGUCAGUUUAUACCUUAAGCCCAGAAAAAUACCACGCACUCUGCUCUCAAACUCAGGUGAUGGAAGUUGGAAAUGAAGAGUAACUGAUUUAUAAAAGCAGGAUGUGUUGAUUUUAAAAUAAAGUGCCUUUAUACAAUGCCUCCUGCUUUGUGUGUUUGGGAAGAGGAGAGAGCAAGGGGUAAUGUACUUUAAUAUAAUGUAAGGAUAUUUCCUUUCUGUGGGUUUACUAAGAUUUCUUCCUGAACGGAAAAGGGGUAUAAUAUUGAGACCAAAAGGAUAUUUCUCUAUUUUGUGAGUUGGUUUCUAAGGUUAGAAGCAUCUUUGUGUGACACGGGCUGGGGACAUCAUGACCCUGUAGAAUUGUGUCGGUUUUGGACUUUAGUUCUUUUCUCCUAUAUUAAUUUCACAUGUAUUGAGCUACCUACUAAGUAGUGAUCAUUAUAAAGGUGAAAACACUCUGCCCUCAAGUUGUUGCAGUCCAGUGGGAGAGGCAGCCGAGUAAAUCAGUGAUACAGUGCUGUAUGUUUUAUGCUGUAAUAGGUAUUUGAGGGGCUAUUUGGGUAUAGAGAAGAAACUUCCUGCUCACAUGGCAGGGGAUGUGGGGAACAGUCAAGGAAGGCUUCUGAAAAAGUCCUGGCCUGAUCUGAGUAGAGAAAGGUGGGUAGGAGUUAACCAGGAAAGCAAGGAUGAAAGCGUGUUGCGUUUAGAUAAAGGAUAGGCUUCAAGGUCAGGGAACGUUGCUGGGUGGUGAGAUGGAACCCUGAUGUGGAGGCUCAGCAGGAAGAAGCAGGAAGGACACUGGGCCCCUGGUGGUUUUAGUUCCAGAAACAAAUGUGGGCCCCAGGGCUCUGCAAUGGUAAGGCUGGAACUACUCAACAUAAGAGCUCCACCUUUAACUGUGCCCCCUAAGAGUACCUGAUGAUCCCCCUAUCUCCUUGUCAAUGUUGCUGUUCUUCUCCAGAAUCUAUUUCAACCCUUCUCUGAUUUCAAACCACCAGUCCCUUUACCUCUCAGAGAAAACAGCAACCACAAAAGCCUCUCCACUUCCUACUAUCUUAAUAUUGACAACUUCCAGAUCAGGGAGCUGAGAUAUCUCAAGCUCAGGUUUCUCUUCUGAGCUUCAGACACUUUUAUCCACUUGGAUUUCACUGGCACAAAACUUUCCAUGUUAGAAUCAAACCCCCCUCCUCCCAGACCUGCUUCUCCCACACACUUCCCUAUCUGAAUGAAAGACACCUCCACUCUCCACCCAGUUGCCAAAUCAGAAAUCUGUCUUUGUUUUCUUUGUCUCACAUUUUCCUAUGUCUAAUCAGUUAAGUUUUAUCAAUACUACCUGUUUAUUUCUUUAAUCUAUUCACAUAUCUUUAUCCUCAAUCUUCAGCAUCCCCUUCCCAUCCUCAGUCUGCUGGUUACUGUAUUUCCUAUUUUACUAAGAAUCUAAAAGAGAUCAGAAGAAAACUUCCACAUCCCCCAACACCCAACCACCAAAUCUGCUAACCCAGUUGCAUUGGUGCUUUUAUAGCCUUCCUUCCUCCCUCUUACUAAGAAUGAACCAACACUAUUCCUAUCAAAGCCCAACCCUCUAGCUUUACAUUGACUCCUAGUGUCUUUUUUCUGGAUUGUCAAUUUUUUUCCUGACCAAUUAUUCUAUUAGCAAUACAAAUAUGCUGUAAAAUCUCUUAAACUUUUUUCUCUGCAUCUUUGAACUGCUGUUCUCUUUUCCUUCUCCCCUUCAUAGCAGAACUCCUCAAAAGAGUUGCUACCUCUAAUUCUUCCCUUCCAGUUCUCUCAUGAACCAGCUACAAUUAAGUAUUCACCCCCACCACUCCAUGGAAACUGCUCUUGUCAAAAUCAUCAAUAGCCUUUGUGUGGUGAAUCCAAUAGCCAGUUUUCAUUCUUCUUACUAAGCUUCUCAUCAGUAUUCCUAGACUAUUUCCUUCACUGGCUUCGACAAAUGCUUUCUUGGUUUUCCUCCAAUUUCUCGACUUUGUUCCUGCUGAAUCUACCUUUUUCUAAUCCGUAAGUGUUGGGGUGUCCCAGGGCUUACUCCUUGGACCUUUUUUCCACCUUUUCCCCUACACUCACCCACUAGGUGAUCUCAAGAAUUUCCAGUUUGAGGCCGGGCGCGGUGGCUCACGCCUGUAAUCCCAGCACUUUGGGAGGCCAAGGCAGGCAGAUCACCUGAGGCCAGGAGUUCGAGACCAGCCUGGCCAACAUGGCAAAACCCUGUCUCCACUAAACCUGCCUCUACUAAAAAUACAAAAAUUAUUAUAUUUUUAUAAAAUUAUUAUAAUUUUAUAAAAUUAUUAUAUUUAUGGAGUACAAUGUGAUGUAAUCCCAGCUACUCGGAAGGCUGUAUGUGUCUAUUUAUGGAGUACAAUGUGCCUGUAAUCCCAGCUACUUGGGAGGCUGAGGCAGGAGAAUCACUUCAACCUAGGAGGCAGAGGUUGUGCUGAGCCAAGAUCGUGCCAUUGCACUCCAGCCUGGGCAACAAGAGAGAAAUAACAUCUCAAAAAAAAAAAAAGAAUUUCCAGUUUUAAAUAUUUACACAAUGUCUCCUAAAUUUAUACCUUCAACCUAGACCUUUCCCUGUGAAUCCCAGUCUCAUUUCCAACAGUCUAAUCAAUGUCUCUAUUUGGAUGUUUAAGAUAUACAAUAGGUAUCAAACUUCCCAUUGUCCACAAUAAACUCUCAAUUUCCGUGCCUUUUCAAACUUACUCCUUCCACAGGCUUUCCCAUCUAGGUAAAUGACACCACCAUUCACCCUGUUGCUUUGGCCAAGAACUUUAGAACUGCCCUUGACUCCCCUCUUUUUCUCAUAUCCUACCUCUACUACAUCAGUAACUCCUGUUGUAUCUCUCUUCAAACUAUAUCCAGAAUUGACCAUGUCCCAAUACUUCCAUUGCUACUGUCUUAGUCCCAGUGUCAUCUUUUACCUGGAUUAUUGUAAAGGCCUCGUAACUAGUCUUCCUGUUUCUGCCCUUCCCUUCUCUGCCCAUCUAUUCUCAACACAGUGUUGCUUUUAAAACAAAGUAAGAUCGUGCCACUCUUCUGCUCUAAAUUCCCCAUUGGUUUCUCAUCUCAAACUAAGGGCCAGUCAUAAUGCCCUCACGGUCCUAUGACAUCUCACUGCACCCCAGCCAUACUCGCCAUCUUACCAUUCUUCUUCUUUUUUGUAAUAAAAACUUUUUACUUUCUUUUUAGUUGACAGAUAAUAAUUGCGUAUAUUUAUGGAGUACAAUGUGAUGUUUUGAUAUAUGUAUGCAUGAGGGAAUGAUUAAAUCAAGCUAAUUAACAUAUUCAUCACUUCAUCUACUCAUCACUUUCUUGUGGUGAAAAUGUUUCAGAUAUACUCUUUAGUAGUUUUCAGGUGUACAGUCGCUGUGGUUUGAGUGCUUUUGUCUUCUCUAAAUUUGAUGUUGACACUUAGUGCCCAGUACAAUGUUACUGGGAGGUGGAGCCUAAUGGGGAUGUUUAAUGGAUUAAUGCCAUUAUAAAAAGGGCUUGCAGGAAUGGGUUCCUUCUCUUUUGCUUUUCUGCCAUAUGAUGACAAAGUGUUCCUCCUCUCUGGAGGAUGCAGCAACAGGCACCAUCUUUGAAGCAGAGAGACCAGGCCCUAACCUUCUGGUGCCUUGAUCUUGGACUUCUCAGCUUCCAGAACUGUGAGAUAAUAAAUUUCUGUUCAUUACAAAUUACCCCAUCUGUGGUAUUCUGUUAUAGCAACACAAAAUGGACUAAGACAACAGUAUACUGUUAUGAACUAUGGUCACCAUGCUGUGCACUAGAUCACAAAAACUUAUUUCUACUGUUUAACUGAAACUUUGUACAUUUUGACUAACAUCUCCCUUUUUCCCAUCAUCCCAUCCCAUUCUUACUAUCGUUGAAGAUGGAGUAUGCCAAGUAGUCCUGAGCCAUGUCCUCACCUCGGGGUGAGCACCUGUUGUUCCUGUGCCUGGAAUGCUCUCCUAGACAUUUGCGUGGCUAGCUCCCUCUUUUCAUUCAGAUCUCAGCUCAUUGUCAUCUCAGAGAGGCCCUCCUUGCCCUCCUUCUACCUCCUGCCUUAGGUAUACUCUGCCACCUUCUGUCAUGGGCUGAAUUGUGUCCCCCCUAAAUCCAUAUGUUGACAUCUUAACCCCUAGUACAGUAAGUCCUCACUUGAUGCUAUCAAUAGGCUCUUGGAAAUGUCGGCUUUCAGUGAAAGGACAUAUAGCAGGUCCUUGAAUAACAUUGUGUUUUGUUCAACAUCGUUGCCUUGUAACACUGAUGAGCAAAACAGUUGGUUCUCUAAUAUGUUGUUUUACUUAAAGCUACAGUUUCCAAGAACCUAUCAAUGAUGUUGAGGACUGAAUGUACCUCAGGUGUAAUGUAUUUGGAGAUAGGGCCUUUUAAGAGGUAAAGUAAAUGAGGUCAUAUGGGUAGGCUGUAAUCCAAUAUGACUGGAAUCCUUAUAAGAAGAGGAAAUGAGGACACAGACACAGAGGGAAGAUGACUAUCUGCAAGUCAAGGAGAGAGGCCUCAGAAGAAACCAAUGCUGCUGACACCACGAUCUUGGACUUCUAGCCUCUAGCACUGUGAGGAAAUAAAUUUCUGUUGUUUAAGCCACCUAGUCUGUGAUACUUUGCUACGGCAGGCCCUAGCAAAUGAAUACACUUGUCUUGUCUUUCCCCCGCCCUGUGAUAUUUAUCAGUGCCGGAUAUUACAUAUUUGUGUAUCUAUAUGCUUAUUUCCCUGACUAAAAUGGAAGCUCCAUGAAGGCAGAUUUCCUCUUGUUCACUGAUGUGUCCCCAGCACCUGGAAUAGUGCCUAGUGCAUGCCAGUGCUCAGACACUUGGACAUUUGAAUGACAUAUCCCCUCUGUCACUUCUCUCCGGGGCCCAAGGCCACCCUCCUAGGUUACCACAGUGGCUUCCUAAUGGGCCAUACCCUCACUUGCUUUCCAUCACCCCCUGAGACCUGGCCCCUGCAUACCUCUCCAGCUUCACCCCUCACAUAUCUCCCUAGCCAGACCUAUAGUAUGUUUAAAAAAAAAGGAAAUCGCACUCCUCUGGCCUCUUUACCUUGGCACACAUUUUUCCAUCACCUGACCCCUGACCCACACUCCCUUUUCCUGUGUAAUCCAAUUAUCUCUAGGCCUCCCGUGUUUCUGUUUGUCCUUCAAUAGAAGGUUGUUUGUCUUGUCUUUUAUUGUAUUUCUAGAACCAAGUGCAGAGACUGUACAAAGUGGACCUCAGCAAAGAUUUACCGAAUGAAUAAAUGAGUUCAGAACGCUGACUUAA